CUCUUGCGCCCUGGUCCAAGAUGGCGGAUGAAGCCACGCGACGUGUUGUGUCUGAGAUCCCGGUGCUGAAGACUAACGCCGGACCCCGAGAUCGUGAGUUGUGGGUGCAGCGACUGAAGGAGGAAUAUCAGUCCCUUAUCCGGUAUGUGGAGAACAACAAGAAUGCUGACAACGAUUGGUUCCGACUGGAGUCCAACAAGGAAGGAACUCGGUGGUUUGGAAAAUGCUGGUAUAUCCAUGACCUCCUGAAAUAUGAGUUUGACAUCGAGUUUGACAUUCCUAUCACAUAUCCUACUACUGCCCCAGAAAUUGCAGUUCCUGAGCUGGAUGGAAAGACAGCAAAGAUGUACAGGGGUGGCAAAAUAUGCCUGACGGAUCAUUUCAAACCUUUGUGGGCCAGGAAUGUGCCCAAAUUUGGACUAGCUCAUCUCAUGGCUCUGGGGCUGGGUCCAUGGCUGGCAGUGGAAAUCCCUGAUCUGAUUCAGAAGGGCGUCAUCCAACACAAAGAGAAAUGCAACCAAUGAAGAAUCAAGCCACUGAGGCAGGGCAGAGGGACCUUUGAUAGGCUACGAUACUAUUUUCCUGUGCAUCACACUUAACUCAUCUAACUGCUUCCCCGGACACCCUCCACCUCUAGUUGUUACUAAGUAGCUGCAGUAGGCAUUGCUGGGGAAGAAACAAACACACACCAAACAGUACUGCUACUUAGUUUCUAAGGCUGCACAGGGAAGGGAAAGACUGGGCUUUGGACAAUCUAGAGGUAAUUUAUAUCCGCCCCCAGGUGGAGCAACAUGCGAUUCUGGAGGCACGGGGGUAACUGAAAGUGAGUACAUAUAGUCUUUCUGGUUUCUGGAGAUAACCCAUCAAUAAAAGCUGCUUCCUCUGGUA